AGUCUCUGAGCAGCCAUUGAAGGGGAAGGAACUGCGGGUGUGUGUGUGUAUGUGUGUGUGUAUGUGUGUGCGCGCGUGCGUGCGUGUGUGUGCGCGCGCUAGUGUGUGGACAAGGAGGUGGGGGCAGCUGAGUUAGAGUCCCAACUCUUGGACUCCAUUUGCUAUUCUCUUCUUUCUCCCCCACACCUAUCUGGUGGUGGUAGUGGGCGUUUAUAUUUGCGUUCCUUUUCAUUCAUUUCUAAAUCUCUUAAAAAUUUUGGGUUGGGGGUAUUGGGGAAGGCAGGAAAGGGAAAAGGAGAGUAGUAGCUGAAGAGCAAGAGGAGGACAUGGAGAUGAAGAAGAAGAUUAACCUGGAGUUAAGGAACAGAUCCCCGGAGGAGGUGACAGAGUUAGUCCUUGAUAAUUGCCUGUGUGUCAAUGGGGAAAUUGAAGGCCUGAAUGAUACUUUCAAAGAACUAGAAUUUCUGAGUAUGGCUAAUGUGGAACUAAGUUCGCUGGCCCGGCUUCCCAGCUUAAAUAAACUUCGAAAAUUGGAGCUUAGUGAUAAUAUAAUUUCUGGAGGCUUGGAAGUCCUGGCAGAGAAAUGUCCAAAUCUUACCUACCUCAAUCUGAGUGGAAACAAAAUAAAAGAUCUCAGUACAGUAGAAGCUCUGCAAAAUCUUAAAAAUUUGAAAAGUCUUGACCUGUUUAACUGUGAGAUCACAAACCUGGAAGAUUAUAGAGAAAGUAUUUUUGAACUACUGCAGCAAAUCACAUACUUAGAUGGAUUUGAUCAGGAGGAUAAUGAAGCGCCGGACUCUGAAGAGGAGGAUGAUGAGGAUGGCGAUGAAGAUGAUGAAGAGGAAGAGGAAAAUGAAGCUGGUCCACCGGAAGGAUAUGAGGAAGAGGAGGAGGAAGAGGAAGAGGAGGAUGAGGAUGAGGAUGAAGAUGAAGAUGAAGCAGGUUCAGAGUUGGGAGAGGGAGAAGAGGAAGUGGGCCUCUCAUACUUAAUGAAAGAAGAAAUUCAGAGUGAAAAAUCAUAUGGAUUUUUCAAUCUUCAAACUGAAUAUUUGAAUUUCAAGGAUGAAGAAGAUGAUGAUGACUAUGUUGAAGAAGGGGAAGAAGAGGAAGAAGAGGAAGAAGGAGGUCUUCGAGGGGAGAAGAGGAAACGAGAUGCUGAAGACGAUGGAGAGGAAGAAGAUGACUAGAUCAUUCUAAGACCAGAUUCUCUAAUGUUUCUGGGUGUGCAAUAGAGUGAUCACAUCUUUGUUUCUUCAUGUACGAUAGCUAUCCCUACAGAAGAUAAUGUGUAACUUUUUAUAGGAAAAGUGUGGUUUUACUAUUUUUGCCUUAUCAUUCCAAAUAAGAACUAGUCUGUUAAUGAUCAUAUUGUAUGUAGAGAAAAAUUUUCAUUGACUCCCAUUGUGGAAUUCCCUAGCAAUUUAUUUAGACUUAAUUUUUUAAAUUCAAGCUUACUGUAUUAGUCAUUUUUAGCCCAUAAUUAAAACAUGAUCACUUUUACACAGGUGUAGUAUGGUGCAUUUCAUUCCUUAUUUAUAAAUUAACUGAAAUUACAGUUUGCUAUAAUAUAAAAUGACAAUAGUCUCUUGAGUGGUAAGUUGGUUAUUUUUUUAGUAGGUGAUCCAGGAAUCUUUAGUUUGAAGGCAGUUACCUUUUUUUUUUUUUUUUUUUGACUAAGAGUGUUUGGUUGCUUUUUUGUCACAAGUAACUUGGAAAAUAGAAGCAGAAUAGUAAAGGUUCUAUUCAGCAACAUAGUUCAUGGAUUUUGUGGAGGUUCUAUUCAGUAAUAUGGUUCAUGGAUUUAGUGGUGACUGAUAAGAUUUUAUUUUUGAAGGAAAAAUUGCUUAUACUAAGUCCAGAGACAUGCAGGUGAGCCCUUUUGUCAGGCUGCAAAUCAUGACAUGCCGAUGGUUGUUUAUUUUGUUUUUAGGUGUGCAUUCUUUUUCUUCUUAGCAAUUCCUUUAUGAUCACCUUCCCUUCUUGUUUCACUCCCUCCCGCUCUCUCAAAAGGAACUUGGGAAACUUGUGAAACCCAGGAAAACCUUUAGUCUUAUACCUCAACUACCUUUCAGUCCUGUCUGGGUUUUAAAUAAGUGAAGUAGAAGAAAUUGAGUAUUUUCUGACAUAAGAAUAUAUUAUCAAUACAGUUUUAUGCAGUAAGCUCUCCUUACCAUAAAUGUUUCUUGGUUGACAACAUCUAAGACAAUAUUAGUGGGAUGAAGAAAGAAAAGCAGGGGUGCUUUUGGAAGCAGUGUUAGUGUUCCUCAAAAGUCGGAACAAUUGCCUGUUGAUAUAUUAAUAAGACAUUAAAGUCAAAUUUUAAUGUUGGCCUCUCAAAUGAUUUGGAUACCACUCUGCAAAGUAUUUCUAACCUUUAAUUCCCAGUUUUAAAACAGAUAUAAUAAUAGCAUUUAAUUGGAAUAUACUAGGCAGCUGGAAAAGUAUUUGAAACUAAAUUGACAUUAAAAUUAAGAUUUGUUUUCAAGUGGAUGUCCAUUAAAAGUAGAAAAAUAUUUGGGAUAAGUGAGUGUGUGUUUCCUUACAUGGCUACUAAAUAAAAUAUAAUGAGUAUACAAGUAUAUCUCCUCUUUUGCUAUGGAGGCUCCAUGUUCAAGGCAAUGGCUUUUUAAAUCUUGGCUAUCUAAAAUUUUUUCCCUUUGUUUUGAAUAUUUGUAAGUUUUUAAGAAGUUAGUGUCAGCAAAUUAAUUGAAGUUAUGCUUCUAUACUGGGACAUAUUUAAAUACUGAGUAUAGUACUGCUGCUACUGCUUCUACAAUGUAAAAUGUAUGACUUGGUGUUUUAAAGUAAAAAUUAUGAUGUUACUUGUGGAGAAACUAAAAAUGUUGUACAACUGACCGAAAGAAAACCCUUGGGGAUAAGUUUAGUGAGGGGAUUGGAAUCCCCAAAAAGAUAACAUUUUUCUUCUGCUUUUAAAAACUGAAAUUCCCUGUUCUAGUUCCUAACAAUUCUCAUUACAUACUAUGCCAGAUUACAAAAUACUUAUUUUUAAAAUGAAAUCUAUAUAUUGACUUUCUUAUCAAUCAUCUUACUGUGCAAUCAAAAUUAGAGUACUUUGGUUUGAAAACAACACUUAGAGCCUCCAGAUAACUUUUAAGACUUAUUUAGCUUUGUGGGUGGUAUUUUCAUGCAAAUAAGUAAGGGUGGGUUUUAUAUUUUGUAGAAGUUUUCGGUCCUAUUUUAAUGCUCUUUGUAUGGCAGUAUGUAUAUAUUGUGUUAAGUUCCUCAAGAAUCUCCUUAAAAACUUUGAAGUUAAUACUUUUGUGCAACUGUGUUUUGAAUAAAGCCAUGACAGUGUUAAAAACAAACAAAAAAAUUUGCAGUACUCCUGAUUAUUCUUUUAUUGUUUUUGACUGUUCCCUGUUUUUUUCUGUGACUGCUGUAACUUAAAGUUUUUGAAACUGAAUUGCUUCAAAUAAAUUGAAGAUUUGUUAUAAUGAUUA